GACGCGCCCGGCGAGACCCUGAGGAUCCAGCUGGCCGCAGGCUAUGGGCUGGGCGGCGGUUGAGACAGCGGCGAUAUUGGGAGGGGUAGGUGAGGGUCGCGAGGCUGCGUGAGCUUCUGAGUGAACGCGGUGCUUUUGGGAACGCGGGACGGGCGACCUGUGGCGCCAGGAGCGGGCCGAGGCGCGGCGGCGCGGCUGCCGUCUGGAUGGGAAGUUACGGUUUACAGCGAAGUCCACCCAGCGUUUCCGAGGUGAAGGCGCCGCGCCAGGCCGGGCGGGCGGCUGGUGAUGGGCAAGCCGGGUGUACCAAGUCCAUGAUGCACAUGAGGAGCAUUUGUAGCCAUCACUGAAUCACCUCAUGACUAGCGGGACAAGCCUCAAAUUCACCGCAGGAUUUCCGAUCUCACUCUGUUGCCCAGGCUGGAGUGCAGUGGCACAAUCACAGCUGACCGCAACCUUGACCUCCCAAGGCUCAGGUGAUCCUCCUGCCUCAGCCCCCAGGUAGCUGGGACCUACAGGCAAUCUGAAAGCAAAUCCUGUUUAGAUGCAGGCGAAGGUUCCUGGUGACCCAGGCUCUCACCUUACCGUCCCUUACCGUCCUCCUGAGGGUGUCCUGGAGCUUCAGUGCUGUGUGUUCUUGGCCUCCACGCUGGGGGUGCCACCAACUCCCACUGUCCAGGGCUUCCAGUGGACUCUCCGAGGUACUGAUGUAGAAACUUCCCCAUUCGGUGCACCAAGAGCAACCUCACACGGUGUGGGCCGAAUGAAGAGCUGCCAGAUCCCACAGCCCUUGAAGAUAAGGAUGGUCAAACAAAAUAAUAUCAUACCUGGAGAAACUCAGAUCUUGGUAAGAUUUACUGGUUGGGAAUCCAAAGUUAAUGCCAAGAAGCAGCCGCCAGUUGGGAUCAAAUGUGAGCCUAUGGAUCAAGACGGUUACCUGGCACGCUGGCCACAAUCUACCUCACUCUUAUCAGAGUCUGAGCUACUGGCAGUGCUUUCAGCUCUGAGUUGAGGCACCUUGAACCUUGUUUUUGUGGUGAAGGAUCCUAAAGUGCUGUGGGGAGUGAUCACAUUUUUCACAACAUCCCUGACUCCACCUCUUCUGCCACAAACGUCAGCAUGGUGGUAUCAGCCGGCCCUUGGUCCAGCGAGAAGGCAGAGAUGAACAUUCUAGAAAUCAACGAGAAAUUGCGCCCCCAGUUGGCAGAGAACAAACAGCAGUUCGGAAACCUCAAAGAGAGAUGUUUUGUAACUCAACUGGCCGGCUUCCUGGCCAACCAGCAGAAGAAAUACAAAUAUGAAGAGUGCAAAGACCUCAUAAAAUCUAUGCUGAGGAAUGAGCGACAGUUCAAGGAGGAGAAGCUUGCAGAGCAGCUCAAGCAAGCUGAGGAGCUCAGGCAAUAUAAAGUCCUGGUUCACGCUCAGGAACGAGAGCUGACCCAGUUAAGGGAGAAGUUGCGGGAAGGGAGAGAUGCCUCCCGCUCAUUGAAUGAGCAUCUCCAGGCCCUCCUUACUCCGGAUGAGCCGGACAAGUCCCAGGGGCAGGACCUCCAAGAACAGCUGGCUGAGGGGUGUAGACUGGCACAGCACCUUGUCCAAAAGCUCAGCCCAGAAAAUGACAACGAUGACGAUGAAGAUGUUCAAGUUGAGUUGGCUGAGAAAGUGCAGAAAUCGUCUGCCCCCAGGGAGAUGCAGAAGGCUGAAGAAAAGGAAGUCCCUGAGGACUCACAGGAGGAAUGUGCCAUCACUUAUUCAAAUAGCCAUGGCCCUUAUGACUCCAACCAGCCACAUAGGAAAACCAAAAUCACAUUUGAGGAAGACAAAGUCGACUCAACUCUGAUUGGCUCAUCCUCUCAUGUUGAAUGGGAGGAUGCUGUACACAUUAUUCCAGAAAAUGAAAGUGAUGAUGAGGAAGAGGAAGAAAAAGGGCCAGUGUCUCCCAGGAAUCUGCAGGAGUCUGAAGAGGAGGAAGUCCCCCAGGAGUCCUGGGAUGAAGGUUAUUCGACUCUCUCAAUUCCUCCUGAAAUGUUGGCCUCGUACCAGUCUUACAGCAGCACAUUUCACUCAUUAGAGGAACAGCAAGUCUGCAUGGCUGUUGACAUAGGCAGACAUCGGUGGGAUCAAGUGAAAAAGGAGGACCAAGAGGCAACAGGUCCCAGGCUCAGCAGGGAGCUGCUGGAUGAGAAAGGGCCUGAAGUCUUGCAGGACUCACUGGAUAGAUGUUAUUCAACUCCUUCAGGUUGUCUUGAACUGACUGACUCAUGCCAGCCCUACAGAAGUGCCUUUUACGUAUUGGAGCAACAGCGUAUUGGCUUGGCUGUUGACAUGGAUGAAAUUGAAAAGUACCAAGAAGUGGAAGAAGACCAAGACCCAUCAUGCCCCAGGCUCAGCAGGGAGCUGCUGGAUGAGAAAGAGCCUGAAGUCUUGCAGGACUCACUGGAUAGAUGUUAUUCGACUCCUUCAGGUUAUCUUGAACUGCCUGACUUAGGCCAGCCCUACAGCAGUGCUGUUUACUCAUUGGAGGAACAGUACCUUGGCUUGGCUCUUGACGUGGACAGAACUAAAAAGGACCAAGAAGAGGAAGAAGACCAAGGCCCACCAUGCCCCAGGCUCAGCAGGGAGCUGCUGGAGGUAGUAGAGCCUGAAGUCUUGCAGGACUCACUGGAUAGAUGUUAUUCAACUCCUUCCAGUUGUCUUGAACAGCCUGACUCCUGCCAGCCCUAUGGAAGUUCCUUUUAUGCAUUGGAGGAAAAACAUGUUGGCUUUUCUCUUGACGUGGGAGAAAUUGAAAAGAAGGGGAAGGGGAAGAAAAGAAGGGGAAGAAGAUCAAAGAAGGAAAGAAGAAGGGGAAGAAAAGAAGGGGAAGAAGAUCAAAACCCACCAUGCCCCAGGCUCAGCAGGGAGCUGCUGGAUGAGAAAGGGCCUGAAGUCUUGCAGGACUCACUGGAUAGAUGUUAUUCAACUCCUUCAGGUUGUCUUGAACUGACUGACUCAUGCCAGCCCUACAGAAGUGCCUUUUACGUAUUGGAGCAACAGCGUGUUGGCUUGGCUGUUGACAUGGAUGAAAUUGAAAAGUACCAAGAAGUGGAAGAAGACCAAGACCCAUCAUGCCCCAGGCUCAGCAGGGAGCUGCUGGAUGAGAAAGAGCCUGAAGUCUUGCAGGACUCACUGGAUAGAUGUUAUUCGACUCCUUCAGGUUAUCUUGAACUGCCUGACUUAGGCCAGCCCUACAGCAGUGCUGUUUACUCAUUGGAGGAACAGUACCUUGGCUUGGCUCUUGACGUGGACAGAACUAAAAAGGACCAAGAAGAGGAAGAAGACCAAGGCCCACCAUGCCCCAGGCUCAGCAGGGAGCUGCUGGAGGUAGUAGAGCCUGAAGUCUUGCAGGACUCACUGGAUAGAUGUUAUUCAACUCCUUCCAGUUGUCUUGAACAGCCUGACUCCUGCCAGCCCUAUGGAAGUUCCUUUUAUGCAUUGGAGGAAAAACAUGUUGGCUUUUCUCUUGACGUGGGAGAAAUUGAAAAGAAGGGGAAGGGGAAGAAAAGAAGGGGAAGAAGAUCAAAGAAGGAAAGAAGAAGGGGAAGAAAAGAAGGGGAAGAAGAUCAAAACCCACCAUGCCCCAGGCUCAGCAGGGAGCUGCUGGAUGAGAAAGGGCCUGAAGUCUUGCAGGACUCACUGGAUAGAAGUUAUUCAACUCCUUCAGGUUGUCUUGAACUGACUGACUCAUGCCAGCCCUACAGAAGUGCCUUUUACGUAUUGGAGCAACAGCGUGUUGGCUUGGCUGUUGACAUGGAUGAAAUUGAAAAGUACCAAGAAGUGGAAGAAGACCAAGACCCAUCAUGCCCCAGGCUCAGCAGGGAGCUGCUGGAUGAGAAAGAGCCUGAAGUCUUGCAGGACUCACUGGAUAGAUGUUAUUCGACUCCUUCAGGUUAUCUUGAACUGCCUGACUUAGGCCAGCCCUACAGCAGUGCUGUUUACUCAUUGGAGGAACAGUACCUUGGCUUGGCUCUUGACGUGGACAGAACUAAAAAGGACCAAGAAGAGGAAGAAGACCAAGGCCCACCAUGCCCCAGGCUCAGCAGGGAGCUGCUGGAGGUAGUAGAGCCUGAAGUCUUGCAGGACUCACUGGAUAGAUGUUAUUCAACUCCUUCCAGUUGUCUUGAACAGCCUGACUCCUGCCAGCCCUAUGGAAGUUCCUUUUAUGCAUUGGAGGAAAAACAUGUUGGCUUUUCUCUCGACGUGGGAGAAAUUGAAAAGAAGGGGAAGGGGAAGAAAAGAAGGGGAAGAAGAUCAAAGAAGGAAAGAAGAAGGGGAAGAAAAGAAGGGGAAGAAGAUCAAAACCCACCAUGCCCCAGGCUCAGCAGGGAGCUGCUGGAUGAGAAAGGGCCUGAAGUCUUGCAGGACUCACUGGAUAGAUGUUAUUCAACUCCUUCAGGUUGUCUUGAACUGACUGACUCAUGCCAGCCCUACAGAAGUGCCUUUUACGUAUUGGAGCAACAGCGUGUUGGCUUGGCUGUUGACAUGGAUGAAAUUGAAAAGUACCAAGAAGUGGAAGAAGACCAAGACCCAUCAUGCCCCAGGCUCAGCAGGGAGCUGCUGGAUGAGAAAGAGCCUGAAGUCUUGCAGGACUCACUGGAUAGAUGUUAUUCGACUCCUUCAGGUUAUCUUGAACUGCCUGACUUAGGCCAGCCCUACAGCAGUGCUGUUUACUCAUUGGAGGAACAGUACCUUGGCUUGGCUCUUGACGUGGACAGAACUAAAAAGGACCAAGAAGAGGAAGAAGACCAAGGCCCACCAUGCCCCAGGCUCAGCAGGGAGCUGCUGGAGGUAGUAGAGCCUGAAGUCUUGCAGGACUCACUGGAUAGAUGUUAUUCAACUCCUUCCAGUUGUCUUGAACAGCCUGACUCCUGCCAGCCCUAUGGAAGUUCCUUUUAUGCAUUGGAGGAAAAACAUGUUGGCUUUUCUCUUGACGUGGGAGAAAUUGAAAAGAAGGGGAAGGGGAAGAAAAGAAGGGGAAGAAGAUCAAAGAAGGAAAGAAGAAGGGGAAGAAAAGAAGGGGAAGAAGAUCAAAACCCACCAUGCCCCAGGCUCAGCAGGGAGCUGCUGGAUGAGAAAGGGCCUGAAGUCUUGCAGGACUCACUGGAUAGAAGUUAUUCAACUCCUUCAGGUUGUCUUGAACUGACUGACUCAUGCCAGCCCUACAGAAGUGCCUUUUACGUAUUGGAGCAACAGCGUGUUGGCUUGGCUGUUGACAUGGAUGAAAUUGAAAAGUACCAAGAAGUGGAAGAAGACCAAGACCCAUCAUGCCCCAGGCUCAGCAGGGAGCUGCUGGAUGAGAAAGAGCCUGAAGUCUUGCAGGACUCACUGGAUAGAUGUUAUUCGACUCCUUCAGGUUAUCUUGAACUGCCUGACUUAGGCCAGCCCUACAGCAGUGCUGUUUACUCAUUGGAGGAACAGUACCUUGGCUUGGCUCUUGACGUGGACAGAACUAAAAAGGACCAAGAAGAGGAAGAAGACCAAGGCCCACCAUGCCCCAGGCUCAGCAGGGAGCUGCUGGAGGUAGUAGAGCCUGAAGUCUUGCAGGACUCACUGGAUAGAUGUUAUUCAACUCCUUCCAGUUGUCUUGAACAGCCUGACUCCUGCCAGCCCUAUGGAAGUUCCUUUUAUGCAUUGGAGGAAAAACAUGUUGGCUUUUCUCUCGACGUGGGAGAAAUUGAAAAGAAGGGGAAGGGGAAGAAAAGAAGGGGAAGAAGAUCAAAGAAGGAAAGAAGAAGGGGAAGAAAAGAAGGGGAAGAAGAUCAAAACCCACCAUGCCCCAGGCUCAGCAGGGAGCUGCUGGAUGAGAAAGGGCCUGAAGUCUUGCAGGACUCACUGGAUAGAAGUUAUUCAACUCCUUCAGGUUGUCUUGAACUGACUGACUCAUGCCAGCCCUACAGAAGUGCCUUUUACGUAUUGGAGCAACAGCGUGUUGGCUUGGCUGUUGACAUGGAUGAAAUUGAAAAGUACCAAGAAGUGGAAGAAGACCAAGACCCAUCAUGCCCCAGGCUCAGCAGGGAGCUGCUGGAUGAGAAAGAGCCUGAAGUCUUGCAGGACUCACUGGAUAGAUGUUAUUCGACUCCUUCAGGUUAUCUUGAACUGCCUGACUUAGGCCAGCCCUACAGCAGUGCUGUUUACUCAUUGGAGGAACAGUACCUUGGCUUGGCUCUUGACGUGGACAGAACUAAAAAGGACCAAGAAGAGGAAGAAGACCAAGGCCCACCAUGCCCCAGGCUCAGCAGGGAGCUGCUGGAGGUAGUAGAGCCUGAAGUCUUGCAGGACUCACUGGAUAGAUGUUAUUCAACUCCUUCCAGUUGUCUUGAACAGCCUGACUCCUGCCAGCCCUAUGGAAGUUCCUUUUAUGCAUUGGAGGAAAAACAUGUUGGCUUUUCUCUCGACGUGGGAGAAAUUGAAAAGAAGGGGAAGGGGAAGAAAAGAAGGGGAAGAAGAUCAAAGAAGGAAAGAAGAAGGGGAAGAAAAGAAGGGGAAGAAGAUCAAACCCCACCAUGCCCCAGGCUCAGCAGGGAGCUGCUGGAUGAGAAAGGGCCUGAAGUCUUGCAGGACUCACUGGAUAGAAGUUAUUCAACUCCUUCAGGUUGUCUUGAACUGACUGACUCAUGCCAGCCCUACAGAAGUGCCUUUUACGUAUUGGAGCAACAGCGUGUUGGCUUGGCUGUUGACAUGGAUGAAAUUGAAAAGUACCAAGAAGUGGAAGAAGACCAAGACCCAUCAUGCCCCAGGCUCAGCAGGGAGCUGCUGGAUGAGAAAGAGCCUGAAGUCUUGCAGGACUCACUGGAUAGAUGUUAUUCGACUCCUUCAGGUUAUCUUGAACUGCCUGACUUAGGCCAGCCCUACAGCAGUGCUGUUUACUCAUUGGAGGAACAGUACCUUGGCUUGGCUCUUGACGUGGACAGAACUAAAAAGGACCAAGAAGAGGAAGAAGACCAAGGCCCACCAUGCCCCAGGCUCAGCAGGGAGCUGCUGGAGGUAGUAGAGCCUGAAGUCUUGCAGGACUCACUGGAUAGAUGUUAUUCAACUCCUUCCAGUUGUCUUGAACAGCCUGACUCCUGCCAGCCCUAUGGAAGUUCCUUUUAUGCAUUGGAGGAAAAACAUGUUGGCUUUUCUCUCGACGUGGGAGAAAUUGAAAAGAAGGGGAAGGGGAAGAAAAGAAGGGGAAGAAGAUCAAAGAAGGAAAGAAGAAGGGGAAGAAAAGAAGGGGAAGAAGAUCAAAACCCACCAUGCCCCAGGCUCAGCAGGGAGCUGCUGGAUGAGAAAGGGCCUGAAGUCUUGCAGGACUCACUGGAUAGAAGUUAUUCAACUCCUUCAGGUUGUCUUGAACUGACUGACUCAUGCCAGCCCUACAGAAGUGCCUUUUACGUAUUGGAGCAACAGCGUGUUGGCUUGGCUGUUGACAUGGAUGAAAUUGAAAAGUACCAAGAAGUGGAAGAAGACCAAGACCCAUCAUGCCCCAGGCUCAGCAGGGAGCUGCUGGAUGAGAAAGAGCCUGAAGUCUUGCAGGACUCACUGGAUAGAUGUUAUUCGACUCCUUCAGGUUAUCUUGAACUGCCUGACUUAGGCCAGCCCUACAGCAGUGCUGUUUACUCAUUGGAGGAACAGUACCUUGGCUUGGCUCUUGACGUGGACAGAACUAAAAAGGACCAAGAAGAGGAAGAAGACCAAGGCCCACCAUGCCCCAGGCUCAGCAGGGAGCUGCUGGAGGUAGUAGAGCCUGAAGUCUUGCAGGACUCACUGGAUAGAUGUUAUUCAACUCCUUCCAGUUGUCUUGAACAGCCUGACUCCUGCCAGCCCUAUGGAAGUUCCUUUUAUGCAUUGGAGGAAAAACAUGUUGGCUUUUCUCUCGACGUGGGAGAAAUUGAAAAGAAGGGGAAGGGGAAGAAAAGAAGGGGAAGAAGAUCAAAGAAGGAAAGAAGAAGGGGAAGAAAAGAAGGGGAAGAAGAUCAAAACCCACCAUGCCCCAGGCUCAGCAGGGAGCUGCUGGAUGAGAAAGGGCCUGAAGUCUUGCAGGACUCACUGGAUAGAUGUUAUUCAACUCCUUCAGGUUGUCUUGAACUGACUGACUCAUGCCAGCCCUACAGAAGUGCCUUUUACGUAUUGGAGCAACAGCGUGUUGGCUUGGCUGUUGACAUGGAUGAAAUUGAAAAGUACCAAGAAGUGGAAGAAGACCAAGACCCAUCAUGCCCCAGGCUCAGCAGGGAGCUGCUGGAUGAGAAAGAGCCUGAAGUCUUGCAGGACUCACUGGAUAGAUGUUAUUCGACUCCUUCAGGUUAUCUUGAACUGCCUGACUUAGGCCAGCCCUACAGCAGUGCUGUUUACUCAUUGGAGGAACAGUACCUUGGCUUGGCUCUUGACGUGGACAGAACUAAAAAGGACCAAGAAGAGGAAGAAGACCAAGGCCCACCAUGCCCCAGGCUCAGCAGGGAGCUGCUGGAGGUAGUAGAGCCUGAAGUCUUGCAGGACUCACUGGAUAGAUGUUAUUCAACUCCUUCCAGUUGUCUUGAACAGCCUGACUCCUGCCAGCCCUAUGGAAGUUCCUUUUAUGCAUUGGAGGAAAAACAUGUUGGCUUUUCUCUCGACGUGGGAGAAAUUGAAAAGAAGGGGAAGGGGAAGAAAAGAAGGGGAAGAAGAUCAAAGAAGGAAAGAAGAAGGGGAAGAAAAGAAGGGGAAGAAGAUCAAAACCCACCAUGCCCCAGGCUCAGCAGGGAGCUGCUGGAUGAGAAAGGGCCUGAAGUCUUGCAGGACUCACUGGAUAGAUGUUAUUCAACUCCUUCAGGUUGUCUUGAACUGACUGACUCAUGCCAGCCCUACAGAAGUGCCUUUUACGUAUUGGAGCAACAGCGUGUUGGCUUGGCUGUUGACAUGGAUGAAAUUGAAAAGUACCAAGAAGUGGAAGAAGACCAAGACCCAUCAUGCCCCAGGCUCAGCAGGGAGCUGCUGGAUGAGAAAGAGCCUGAAGUCUUGCAGGACUCACUGGAUAGAUGUUAUUCGACUCCUUCAGGUUAUCUUGAACUGCCUGACUUAGGCCAGCCCUACAGCAGUGCUGUUUACUCAUUGGAGGAACAGUACCUUGGCUUGGCUCUUGACGUGGACAGAACUAAAAAGGACCAAGAAGAGGAAGAAGACCAAGGCCCACCAUGCCCCAGGCUCAGCAGGGAGCUGCUGGAGGUAGUAGAGCCUGAAGUCUUGCAGGACUCACUGGAUAGAUGUUAUUCAACUCCUUCCAGUUGUCUUGAACAGCCUGACUCCUGCCAGCCCUAUGGAAGUUCCUUUUAUGCAUUGGAGGAAAAACAUGUUGGCUUUUCUCUCGACGUGGGAGAAAUUGAAAAGAAGGGGAAGGGGAAGAAAAGAAGGGGAAGAAGAUCAAAGAAGGAAAGAAGAAGGGGAAGAAAAGAAGGGGAAGAAGAUCAAAACCCACCAUGCCCCAGGCUCAGCAGGGAGCUGCUGGAUGAGAAAGGGCCUGAAGUCUUGCAGGACUCACUGGAUAGAUGUUAUUCAACUCCUUCAGGUUGUCUUGAACUGACUGACUCAUGCCAGCCCUACAGAAGUGCCUUUUACGUAUUGGAGCAACAGCGUGUUGGCUUGGCUGUUGACAUGGAUGAAAUUGAAAAGUACCAAGAAGUGGAAGAAGACCAAGACCCAUCAUGCCCCAGGCUCAGCAGGGAGCUGCUGGAUGAGAAAGAGCCUGAAGUCUUGCAGGACUCACUGGAUAGAUGUUAUUCGACUCCUUCAGGUUAUCUUGAACUGCCUGACUUAGGCCAGCCCUACAGCAGUGCUGUUUACUCAUUGGAGGAACAGUACCUUGGCUUGGCUCUUGACGUGGACAGAACUAAAAAGGACCAAGAAGAGGAAGAAGACCAAGGCCCACCAUGCCCCAGGCUCAGCAGGGAGCUGCUGGAGGUAGUAGAGCCUGAAGUCUUGCAGGACUCACUGGAUAGAUGUUAUUCAACUCCUUCCAGUUGUCUUGAACAGCCUGACUCCUGCCAGCCCUAUGGAAGUUCCUUUUAUGCAUUGGAGGAAAAACAUGUUGGCUUUUCUCUCGACGUGGGAGAAAUUGAAAAGAAGGGGAAGGGGAAGAAAAGAAGGGGAAGAAGAUCAAAGAAGGAAAGAAGAAGGGGAAGAAAAGAAGGGGAAGAAGAUCAAAACCCACCAUGCCCCAGGCUCAGCAGGGAGCUGCUGGAUGAGAAAGGGCCUGAAGUCUUGCAGGACUCACUGGAUAGAAGUUAUUCAACUCCUUCAGGUUGUCUUGAACUGACUGACUCAUGCCAGCCCUACAGAAGUGCCUUUUACGUAUUGGAGCAACAGCGUGUUGGCUUGGCUGUUGACAUGGAUGAAAUUGAAAAGUACCAAGAAGUGGAAGAAGACCAAGACCCAUCAUGCCCCAGGCUCAGCAGGGAGCUGCUGGAUGAGAAAGAGCCUGAAGUCUUGCAGGACUCACUGGAUAGAUGUUAUUCGACUCCUUCAGGUUAUCUUGAACUGCCUGACUUAGGCCAGCCCUACAGCAGUGCUGUUUACUCAUUGGAGGAACAGUACCUUGGCUUGGCUCUUGACGUGGACAGAACUAAAAAGGACCAAGAAGAGGAAGAAGACCAAGGCCCACCAUGCCCCAGGCUCAGCAGGGAGCUGCUGGAGGUAGUAGAGCCUGAAGUCUUGCAGGACUCACUGGAUAGAUGUUAUUCAACUCCUUCCAGUUGUCUUGAACAGCCUGACUCCUGCCAGCCCUAUGGAAGUUCCUUUUAUGCAUUGGAGGAAAAACAUGUUGGCUUUUCUCUUGACGUGGGAGAAAUUGAAAAGAAGGGGAAGGGGAAGAAAAGAAGGGGAAGAAGAUCAAAGAAGGAAAGAAGAAGGGGAAGAAAAGAAGGGGAAGAAGAUCAAAACCCACCAUGCCCCAGGCUCAGCAGGGAGCUGCUGGAUGAGAAAGGGCCUGAAGUCUUGCAGGACUCACUGGAUAGAAGUUAUUCAACUCCUUCAGGUUGUCUUGAACUGACUGACUCAUGCCAGCCCUACAGAAGUGCCUUUUACGUAUUGGAGCAACAGCGUGUUGGCUUGGCUGUUGACAUGGAUGAAAUUGAAAAGUACCAAGAAGUGGAAGAAGACCAAGACCCAUCAUGCCCCAGGCUCAGCAGGGAGCUGCUGGAUGAGAAAGAGCCUGAAGUCUUGCAGGACUCACUGGAUAGAUGUUAUUCGACUCCUUCAGGUUAUCUUGAACUGCCUGACUUAGGCCAGCCCUACAGCAGUGCUGUUUACUCAUUGGAGGAACAGUACCUUGGCUUGGCUCUUGACGUGGACAGAACUAAAAAGGACCAAGAAGAGGAAGAAGACCAAGGCCCACCAUGCCCCAGGCUCAGCAGGGAGCUGCUGGAGGUAGUAGAGCCUGAAGUCUUGCAGGACUCACUGGAUAGAUGUUAUUCAACUCCUUCCAGUUGUCUUGAACAGCCUGACUCCUGCCAGCCCUAUGGAAGUUCCUUUUAUGCAUUGGAGGAAAAACAUGUUGGCUUUUCUCUCGACGUGGGAGAAAUUGAAAAGAAGGGGAAGGGGAAGAAAAGAAGGGGAAGAAGAUCAAAGAAGGAAAGAAGAAGGGGAAGAAAAGAAGGGGAAGAAGAUCAAAACCCACCAUGCCCCAGGCUCAGCAGGGAGCUGCUGGAUGAGAAAGGGCCUGAAGUCUUGCAGGACUCACUGGAUAGAAGUUAUUCAACUCCUUCAGGUUGUCUUGAACUGACUGACUCAUGCCAGCCCUACAGAAGUGCCUUUUACGUAUUGGAGCAACAGCGUGUUGGCUUGGCUGUUGACAUGGAUGAAAUUGAAAAGUACCAAGAAGUGGAAGAAGACCAAGACCCAUCAUGCCCCAGGCUCAGCAGGGAGCUGCUGGAUGAGAAAGAGCCUGAAGUCUUGCAGGACUCACUGGAUAGAUGUUAUUCGACUCCUUCAGGUUAUCUUGAACUGCCUGACUUAGGCCAGCCCUACAGCAGUGCUGUUUACUCAUUGGAGGAACAGUACCUUGGCUUGGCUCUUGACGUGGACAGAACUAAAAAGGACCAAGAAGAGGAAGAAGACCAAGGCCCACCAUGCCCCAGGCUCAGCAGGGAGCUGCUGGAGGUAGUAGAGCCUGAAGUCUUGCAGGACUCACUGGAUAGAUGUUAUUCAACUCCUUCCAGUUGUCUUGAACAGCCUGACUCCUGCCAGCCCUAUGGAAGUUCCUUUUAUGCAUUGGAGGAAAAACAUGUUGGCUUUUCUCUUGACGUGGGAGAAAUUGAAAAGAAGGGGAAGGGGAAGAAAAGAAGGGGAAGAAGAUCAAAGAAGGAAAGAAGAAGGGGAAGAAAAGAAGGGGAAGAAGAUCAAAACCCACCAUGCCCCAGGCUCAGCAGGGAGCUGCUGGAUGAGAAAGGGCCUGAAGUCUUGCAGGACUCACUGGAUAGAAGUUAUUCAACUCCUUCAGGUUGUCUUGAACUGACUGACUCAUGCCAGCCCUACAGAAGUGCCUUUUACGUAUUGGAGCAACAGCGUGUUGGCUUGGCUGUUGACAUGGAUGAAAUUGAAAAGUACCAAGAAGUGGAAGAAGACCAAGACCCAUCAUGCCCCAGGCUCAGCAGGGAGCUGCUGGAUGAGAAAGAGCCUGAAGUCUUGCAGGACUCACUGGAUAGAUGUUAUUCGACUCCUUCAGGUUAUCUUGAACUGCCUGACUUAGGCCAGCCCUACAGCAGUGCUGUUUACUCAUUGGAGGAACAGUACCUUGGCUUGGCUCUUGACGUGGACAGAACUAAAAAGGACCAAGAAGAGGAAGAAGACCAAGGCCCACCAUGCCCCAGGCUCAGCAGGGAGCUGCUGGAGGUAGUAGAGCCUGAAGUCUUGCAGGACUCACUGGAUAGAUGUUAUUCAACUCCUUCCAGUUGUCUUGAACAGCCUGACUCCUGCCAGCCCUAUGGAAGUUCCUUUUAUGCAUUGGAGGAAAAACAUGUUGGCUUUUCUCUUGACGUGGGAGAAAUUGAAAAGAAGGGGAAGGGGAAGAAAAGAAGGGGAAGAAGAUCAAAGAAGGAAAGAAGAAGGGGAAGAAAAGAAGGGGAAGAAGAUCAAAACCCACCAUGCCCCAGGCUCAGCAGGGAGCUGCUGGAUGAGAAAGGGCCUGAAGUCUUGCAGGACUCACUGGAUAGAUGUUAUUCAACUCCUUCAGGUUGUCUUGAACUGACUGACUCAUGCCAGCCCUACAGAAGUGCCUUUUACGUAUUGGAGCAACAGCGUGUUGGCUUGGCUGUUGACAUGGAUGAAAUUGAAAAGUACCAAGAAGUGGAAGAAGACCAAGACCCAUCAUGCCCCAGGCUCAGCAGGGAGCUGCUGGAUGAGAAAGAGCCUGAAGUCUUGCAGGACUCACUGGAUAGAUGUUAUUCGACUCCUUCAGGUUAUCUUGAACUGCCUGACUUAGGCCAGCCCUACAGCAGUGCUGUUUACUCAUUGGAGGAACAGUACCUUGGCUUGGCUCUUGACGUGGACAGAACUAAAAAGGACCAAGAAGAGGAAGAAGACCAAGGCCCACCAUGCCCCAGGCUCAGCAGGGAGCUGCUGGAGGUAGUAGAGCCUGAAGUCUUGCAGGACUCACUGGAUAGAUGUUAUUCAACUCCUUCCAGUUGUCUUGAACAGCCUGACUCCUGCCAGCCCUAUGGAAGUUCCUUUUAUGCAUUGGAGGAAAAACAUGUUGGCUUUUCUCUUGACGUGGGAGAAAUUGAAAAGAAGGGGAAGGGGAAGAAAAGAAGGGGAAGAAGAUCAAAGAAGGAAAGAAGAAGGGGAAGAAAAGAAGGGGAAGAAGAUCAAAACCCACCAUGCCCCAGGCUCAGCAGGGAGCUGCUGGAUGAGAAAGGGCCUGAAGUCUUGCAGGACUCACUGGAUAGAUGUUAUUCAACUCCUUCAGGUUGUCUUGAACUGACUGACUCAUGCCAGCCCUACAGAAGUGCCUUUUACGUAUUGGAGCAACAGCGUGUUGGCUUGGCUGUUGACAUGGAUGAAAUUGAAAAGUACCAAGAAGUGGAAGAAGACCAAGACCCAUCAUGCCCCAGGCUCAGCAGGGAGCUGCUGGAUGAGAAAGAGCCUGAAGUCUUGCAGGACUCACUGGAUAGAUGUUAUUCGACUCCUUCAGGUUAUCUUGAACUGCCUGACUUAGGCCAGCCCUACAGCAGUGCUGUUUACUCAUUGGAGGAACAGUACCUUGGCUUGGCUCUUGACGUGGACAGAACUAAAAAGGACCAAGAAGAGGAAGAAGACCAAGGCCCACCAUGCCCCAGGCUCAGCAGGGAGCUGCUGGAGGUAGUAGAGCCUGAAGUCUUGCAGGACUCACUGGAUAGAUGUUAUUCAACUCCUUCCAGUUGUCUUGAACAGCCUGACUCCUGCCAGCCCUAUGGAAGUUCCUUUUAUGCAUUGGAGGAAAAACAUGUUGGCUUUUCUCUUGACGUGGGAGAAAUUGAAAAGAAGGGGAAGGGGAAGAAAAGAAGGGGAAGAAGAUCAAAGAAGGAAAGAAGAAGGGGAAGAAAAGAAGGGGAAGAAGAUCAAACCCCACCAUGCCCCAGGCUCAGCAGGGAGCUGCUGGAUGAGAAAGGGCCUGAAGUCUUGCAGGACUCACUGGAUAGAUGUUAUUCAACUCCUUCAGGUUGUCUUGAACUGACUGACUCAUGCCAGCCCUACAGAAGUGCCUUUUACGUAUUGGAGCAACAGCGUGUUGGCUUGGCUGUUGACAUGGAUGAAAUUGAAAAGUACCAAGAAGUGGAAGAAGACCAAGACCCAUCAUGCCCCAGGCUCAGCAGGGAGCUGCUGGAUGAGAAAGAGCCUGAAGUCUUGCAGGACUCACUGGAUAGAUGUUAUUCGACUCCUUCAGGUUAUCUUGAACUGCCUGACUUAGGCCAGCCCUACAGCAGUGCUGUUUACUCAUUGGAGGAACAGUACCUUGGCUUGGCUCUUGACGUGGACAGAACUAAAAAGGACCAAGAAGAGGAAGAAGACCAAGGCCCACCAUGCCCCAGGCUCAGCAGGGAGCUGCUGGAGGUAGUAGAGCCUGAAGUCUUGCAGGACUCACUGGAUAGAUGUUAUUCAACUCCUUCCAGUUGUCUUGAACAGCCUGACUCCUGCCAGCCCUAUGGAAGUUCCUUUUAUGCAUUGGAGGAAAAACAUGUUGGCUUUUCUCUUGACGUGGGAGAAAUUGAAAAGAAGGGGAAGGGGAAGAAAAGAAGGGGAAGAAGAUCAAAGAAGGAAAGAAGAAGGGGAAGAAAAGAAGGGGAAGAAGAUCAAAACCCACCAUGCCCCAGGCUCAGCAGGGAGCUGCUGGAUGAGAAAGAGCCUGAAGUCUUGCAGGACUCACUGGAUAGAUGUUAUUCGACUCCUUCAGGUUAUCUUGAACUGCCUGACUUAGGCCAGCCCUACAGCAGUGCUGUUUACUCAUUGGAGGAACAGUACCUUGGCUUGGCUCUUGACGUGGACAGAACUAAAAAGGACCAAGAAGAGGAAGAAGACCAAGGCCCACCAUGCCCCAGGCUCAGCAGGGAGCUGCUGGAGGUAGUAGAGCCUGAAGUCUUGCAGGACUCACUGGAUAGAUGUUAUUCAACUCCUUCCAGUUGUCUUGAACAGCCUGACUCCUGCCAGCCCUAUGGAAGUUCCUUUUAUGCAUUGGAGGAAAAACAUGUUGGCUUUUCUCUUGACGUGGGAGAAAUUGAAAAGAAGGGGAAGGGGAAGAAAAGAAGGGGAAGAAGAUCAAAGAAGGAAAGAAGAAGGGGAAGAAAAGAAGGGGAAGAAGAUCAAAACCCACCAUGCCCCAGGCUCAGCAGGGAGCUGCUGGAUGAGAAAGAGCCUGAAGUCUUGCAGGACUCACUGGAUAGAUGUUAUUCGACUCCUUCAGGUUAUCUUGAACUGCCUGACUUAGGCCAGCCCUACAGCAGUGCUGUUUACUCAUUGGAGGAACAGUACCUUGGCUUGGCUCUUGACGUGGACAGAACUAAAAAGGACCAAGAAGAGGAAGAAGACCAAGGCCCACCAUGCCCCAGGCUCAGCAGGGAGCUGCUGGAGGUAGUAGAGCCUGAAGUCUUGCAGGACUCACUGGAUAGAUGUUAUUCAACUCCUUCCAGUUGUCUUGAACAGCCUGACUCCUGCCAGCCCUAUGGAAGUUCCUUUUAUGCAUUGGAGGAAAAACAUGUUGGCUUUUCUCUUGACGUGGGAGAAAUUGAAAAGAAGGGGAAGGGGAAGAAAAGAAGGGGAAGAAGAUCAAAGAAGGAAAGAAGAAGGGGAAGAAAAGAAGGGGAAGAAGAUCAAAACCCACCAUGCCCCAGGCUCAGCAGGGAGCUGCUGGAUGAGAAAGGGCCUGAAGUCUUGCAGGACUCACUGGAUAGAAGUUAUUCAACUCCUUCAGGUUGUCUUGAACUGACUGACUCAUGCCAGCCCUACAGAAGUGCCUUUUACGUAUUGGAGCAACAGCGUGUUGGCUUGGCUGUUGACAUGGAUGAAAUUGAAAAGUACCAAGAAGUGGAAGAAGACCAAGACCCAUCAUGCCCCAGGCUCAGCAGGGAGCUGCUGGAUGAGAAAGAGCCUGAAGUCUUGCAGGACUCACUGGAUAGAUGUUAUUCGACUCCUUCAGGUUAUCUUGAACUGCCUGACUUAGGCCAGCCCUACAGCAGUGCUGUUUACUCAUUGGAGGAACAGUACCUUGGCUUGGCUCUUGACGUGGACAGAACUAAAAAGGACCAAGAAGAGGAAGAAGACCAAGGCCCACCAUGCCCCAGGCUCAGCAGGGAGCUGCUGGAGGUAGUAGAGCCUGAAGUCUUGCAGGACUCACUGGAUAGAUGUUAUUCAACUCCUUCCAGUUGUCUUGAACAGCCUGACUCCUGCCAGCCCUAUGGAAGUUCCUUUUAUGCAUUGGAGGAAAAACAUGUUGGCUUUUCUCUCGACGUGGGAGAAAUUGAAAAGAAGGGGAAGGGGAAGAAAAGAAGGGGAAGAAGAUCAAAGAAGGAAAGAAGAAGGGGAAGAAAAGAAGGGGAAGAAGAUCAAAACCCACCAUGCCCCAGGCUCAGCAGGGAGCUGCUGGAUGAGAAAGGGCCUGAAGUCUUGCAGGACUCACUGGAUAGAUGUUAUUCAACUCCUUCAGGUUGUCUUGAACUGACUGACUCAUGCCAGCCCUACAGAAGUGCCUUUUACGUAUUGGAGCAACAGCGUGUUGGCUUGGCUGUUGACAUGGAUGAAAUUGAAAAGUACCAAGAAGUGGAAGAAGACCAAGACCCAUCAUGCCCCAGGCUCAGCAGGGAGCUGCUGGAUGAGAAAGAGCCUGAAGUCUUGCAGGACUCACUGGAUAGAUGUUAUUCGACUCCUUCAGGUUAUCUUGAACUGCCUGACUUAGGCCAGCCCUACAGCAGUGCUGUUUACUCAUUGGAGGAACAGUACCUUGGCUUGGCUCUUGACGUGGACAGAACUAAAAAGGACCAAGAAGAGGAAGAAGACCAAGGCCCACCAUGCCCCAGGCUCAGCAGGGAGCUGCUGGAGGUAGUAGAGCCUGAAGUCUUGCAGGACUCACUGGAUAGAUGUUAUUCAACUCCUUCCAGUUGUCUUGAACAGCCUGACUCCUGCCAGCCCUAUGGAAGUUCCUUUUAUGCAUUGGAGGAAAAACAUGUUGGCUUUUCUCUUGACGUGGGAGAAAUUGAAAAGAAGGGGAAGGGGAAGAAAAGAAGGGGAAGAAGAUCAAAGAAGAAAAGAAGAAGGGGAAGAAAAGAAGGGGAAGAAGAUCAAAACCCACCAUGCCCCAGGCUCAACGGCGUGCUGAUGGAAGUGGAAGAGCCUGAAGUCUUACAGGACUCACUGGAUGGAUGUUAUUCUACUCCGUCAAUGUACUUUGAACUACCUGACUCAUUCCAGCACUACAGAAGUGUGUUUUACUCAUUUGAGGAACAGCACAUCAGCUUCGCCCUUUACGUGGACAAUAGGUUUUUUACUUUGACGGUGACAAGUCUCCACCUGGUGUUCCAGAUGGGAGUCAUAUUCCCACAAUAAACAGCCCUUACUAAGCCGAGAGAUGUCAUUCCUGCAGGCAGGACCUAUAGGCACGUGAAGAUUUGAAUGAAAGUACAGUUCCAUUUGGAAGCCCAGACAUAGGAUGGGUCAGUGGGCAUGGCUGUAUUCCUAUUCUCAAACCAUGCCAGUGGCAACCUGUGCUCAGUCUGAAGACAAUGGACCCACGUUAGGUGUGACACGUUCACAUAACUGUGCAGCACAUGCCGGGAGUGAUCAGUCAGACAUUUUAAUUUGAACCACGUAUCUCUGGGUAGCUACAAAAUUCCUCAGGGAUUUCAUUUUGCAGGCAUGUCUCUGAGCUUCUAUACCUGCUCAAGGUCAUUGUCAUCUUUGUGUUUAGCUCAUCCAAAGGUGUUACCCUGGUUUCAAUGAACCUAACCUCAUUCUUUGUGUCUUCAGUGUUGGCUUGUUUUAGCUGAUCCAUCUGUAACACAGGAGGGAUCCUUGGUUGAGGAUUGUAUUUCAGAACCACCAACUGCUCUUGACAAUUGUUAACCCGCUAGGCUCCUUUGGUUAGAGAAGCCACAGUCCUUCAGCCUCCAAUUGGUGUCAGUACUUAGGAAGACCACAGCUAGAUGGACAAACAGCAUUGGGAGGCCUUAGCCCUGCUCUUCUCAAUUCCAUCCUGUAGAGAACAGGAGUCAGGAGCCGCUGGCAGGAGACAGCAUGUCACCCAGGACUCUGCCGGUGCAGAAUAUGAACAAUGCCAUGUUCUUGCAGAAAACGCUUAGCCUGAGUUUCAUAGGAGGUAAUCACCAGACAACUGCAGAAUGUAGAACACUGAGCAGGACAACUGACCUGUCUCCUUCACAUAGUCCAUAUCACCACAAAUCACACAACAAAAAGGAGAAGAGAUAUUUUGGGUUCAAAAAACGUAAAAAGAUAAUGUAGCUGCAUUUCUUUAGUUAUUUUGAACCCCAAAUAUUUCCUCAUCUUUUUGUUGUUGUCAUGGAUGGUGGUGACAUGGACUUGUUUAUAGAGGACAGGUCAGCUGUCUGGCUCAAUGAUCUACAUUCUGAAGUUGUCUGAAAAUGUCUUCAUGAUUAAAUUCAGCCUAAACGUUUUGCCGGGAACACUGCAGAGACAAUGCUGUGAGUUUCCAACCUCAGCCCAUCUGCGGGCAGAGAAGGUCUAGUUUGUCCAUCACCAUUAUGAUAUCAGGACUGGUUACUUGGUUAAGGAGGGGUCUAGGAGAUCUGUCCCUUUUAGAGACACCUUACUUAUAAUGAAGAAGUACUUGGGAAAGCGGUUUUCAAGAGUAUAAAUAUCCUGUAUUCUAAUGAUCAUCCUCUAAACAUUUUAUCAUUUAUUAAUCCUCCCUGCCUGUGUCUAUUAUUAUAUUCAUAUCUCUACACUGCAAAUUUUGGGUCUCAAUUUUUACUGUGCCUUUGUUUUUACUAGUGUCUGCUGUUGCAAAAAGAAGAAGACAUUCUCUGCCUGAGUUUUAAUUUUUGUCCAAAGUUAAUUUUAAUCUAUACAAUUAAAACCUUUUGCCUAUCA